UUUUGAAAGCAGUGAUAUAACUCUAGGUAAAUGCUAUGUCUACUAAUUAUAGUUUCUUAAUUUUCAUAGCUAUAUUAUGAAAAGAGUAAAUUGAAGAAAUGGAAACUGCAAAUUACACCAAGGUGACAGAAUUUGUUCUCACUGGCCUAUCCCAGACUCCAGAGGUCCAACUAGUCCUAUUUGUUAUAUUUCUAUCCUUCUAUUUGUUCAUCCUACCAGGAAAUAUCCUUAUCAUUUGCACCAUCAGUCUAGACCCUCAUCUGACCUCUCCUAUGUAUUUCCUGUUGGCUAAUCUGGCCUUCCUUGAUAUUUGGUACUCUUCCAUUACAGCCCCUGAAAUGCUCAUAGACUUCUUUGUGGAGAGGAAGAUAAUUUCUUUUGAUGAAUGCAUUGCACAGCUCUUCUUCUUACACUUUGCUGGGGCUUCAGAGAUGUUCUUGCUCACAGUGAUGGCCUUUGACCUCUACACUGCUAUCUGCCGACCCCUCCACUAUGCUACCAUCAUGAAUCAACGUCUCUGCUGUAUCCUGGUGGCUCUCUCCUGGAGGGGGGGCUUCAUUCAUUCUAUCAUACAGGUGGCUCUCAUUGUUCGACUUCCUUUCUGUGGGCCCAAUGAGUUAGACAGUUACUUCUGUGACAUCACACAGGUUGUCCGGAUUGCCUGUGCCAACACCUUCCCAGAGGAGUUAGUGAUGAUCUGUAGUAGUGGUCUGAUCUCUGUGGUGUGUUUGAUUGCUCUGUUAAUGUCCUAUGCCUUCCUUCUGGCCUUGCUCAAGAAACUUUCAGGCUCAGGUGAGAAUACCAACAGGGCCGUGUCCACCUGCUAUUCCCACAUUACCAUUGUGGUGCUAAUGUUUGGGCCAUCCAUCUACAUUUAUGCUCGCCCAUUUGACUCGUUUUCCCUAGAUAAAGUGGUGUCUGUGUUCAAUACUUUAAUAUUCCCUUUACAUAAUCCCAUUAUUUACACAUUGAGAAACAAGGAAGUAAAGGCAGCCAUGAGGAAGUUGGUCACCAAAUAUAUUUUGUGUAAAGAGAAGUGAAAGAUAAAUUAUACAUUUUAUAGUUCCCCUGAGGAUCAUUGUCC